AGGCCCUGCCACGCUGCUUCAUGAGAUGGAGAUAUACAGCUCCUCAGGGCAGGGUUGGUGAGAAUAUCCAAAAAAAAAGGAGGUUAAGCACCUGACACUGCUUGGGAAACAAAGGAGGCACUCAGGGUGGCCCCGCAAUGGAAGUCGCUGCUCAGGGGGUUAAUGCAGGCUGUGAAACAGGGCCACCUGCAACCGUGGCUUUUCAAAGCUGAAGCCAUACCCUGGAGGGAGAGAGGAUCCUUGGGCACUGACCCUGGCUGUCCACAGCUAAAUGAUCAUGGGACACCCAUGACCAUGGGCGUGGCUGGAGGAGGCCCUGCCCUCAGGGGUCUAUUGGCAUCCAGGGGAAGUGUCUACGGGGUAAUGAUUAACCCACACCUGCCACCUGGUUUUCAGCCUUCUUGCCCUGCUGACUCAUUUUGCAAAUCCCACUUGCAAAAUUUGGGAGCAGCCUGGGUCCAGCCCCCGCCACGCCACCUCACCUGAGAUUCCAGCAGUGGAGGUGCUGCGUCGCCGGGUGGGGUGGCCCUGGCAUUCGGACCUGCCACUGGGAAGCCCGAGGCCGGCAUGUGGGAGGCGAGUGGGAUGGAGGAAAGAGCGAUGGAAGAGCUGGCGAUGGAGGAGACAGCGCUGGACCCUCUGCUGGCAGAGGCCGCCGGGGCCGUGGAUGGGGAGGGCGCGCCGCCCGGCGGUCCCAGCGCACAGGCGGCCACGAUGAGGGUCAACGAGAAGUACUCGACGCUCCCGGCCGAGGACCGCAGCGUCCACAUCAUCAACAUCUGCGCCAUCGAGGACAUCGGCUACCUGCCGUCCGAGGGCACGCUGCUGAACUCCUUAUCUGUGGACCCUGAUGCCGAGUGCAAGUAUGGCCUGUACUUCAGGGACGGCCGGCGCAAGGUGGACUACAUCCUGGUGUACCAUCACAAGAGGCCCUCGGGCAACCGGACCCUGGUCAGGAGGGUGCAGCACAGCGACACCCCCUCUGGGGCUCGCAGCGUCAAGCAGGACCACCCCCUGCCGGGCAAGGGGGCGUCGCUGGAUGCAGGCUCGGGGGAGCCCCCGAUGGACUACCACGAGGAUGACAAGCGCUUCCGCAGGGAGGAGUACGAGGGCAACCUCCUGGAGGCGGGCCUGGAGCUGGAGCGGGACGAGGACACUAAAAUCCACGGAGUCGGGUUUGUGAAAAUCCAUGCCCCCUGGAACGUGCUGUGCAGAGAGGCCGAGUUUCUGAAACUGAAGAUGCCGACGAAGAAGAUGUACCACAUUAAUGAGACCCGUGGCCUCCUGAAAAAAAUCAACUCUGUGCUCCAGAAAAUCACAGAUCCCAUCCAGCCCAAAGUGGCUGAGCACAGGCCCCAGACCAUGAAGAGACUCUCCUAUCCCUUCUCCCGGGAGAAGCAGCAUCUAUUUGACUUGUCUGAUAAGGAUUCCUUUUUCGACAGCAAAACCCGGAGCACGAUUGUCUAUGAGAUCUUGAAGAGAACGACGUGUACAAAGGCCAAGUACAGCAUGGGCAUCACGAGCCUGCUGGCCAAUGGUGUGUACGCGGCUGCAUACCCACUGCACGAUGGAGACUACAACGGUGAAAACGUCGAGUUCAACGACAGAAAACUCCUGUACGAAGAGUGGGCACGCUAUGGAGUUUUCUAUAAGUACCAGCCCAUCGACCUGGUCAGGAAGUAUUUUGGGGAGAAGAUCGGCCUGUACUUCGCCUGGCUGGGCGUGUACACCCAGAUGCUCAUCCCUGCCUCCAUCGUGGGAAUCAUUGUCUUCCUGUACGGAUGCGCCACCAUGGAUGAAAACAUCCCCAGCAUGGAGAUGUGUGACCAGAGACACAAUAUCACCAUGUGCCCGCUUUGCGACAAGACCUGCAGCUACUGGAAGAUGAGCUCAGCCUGCGCCACGGCCCGCGCCAGCCACCUCUUCGACAACCCCGCCACGGUCUUCUUCUCUGUCUUCAUGGCCCUCUGGGCUGCCACCUUCAUGGAGCACUGGAAGCGGAAACAGAUGCGACUCAACUACCGCUGGGACCUCACGGGCUUUGAAGAGGAAGAGGAUCAUCCUAGAGCUGAAUACGAAGCCAGAGUCUUGGAGAAGUCUCUGAAGAAAGAGUCCAGAAACAAAGAGACUGACAAAGUGAAGCUGACAUGGAGAGAUCGGUUCCCAGCCUACCUCACUAACUUGGUCUCCAUCAUCUUCAUGAUUGCAGUGACGUUUGCCAUCGUCCUCGGCGUCAUCAUCUACAGAAUCUCCAUGGCCGCCGCCUUGGCCAUGAACUCCUCCCCCUCCGUGCGGUCCAACAUCCGGGUCACAGUCACAGCCACCGCAGUCAUCAUCAACCUAGUGGUCAUCAUCCUCCUGGACGAGGUGUAUGGCUGCAUAGCCCGAUGGCUCACCAAGAUCGAGGUCCCAAAGACGGAGAAAAGCUUUGAGGAGAGGCUGAUCUUCAAGGCUUUCCUGCUGAAGUUUGUGAAUUCCUACACCCCCAUCUUUUACGUGGCGUUCUUCAAAGGCCGGUUUGUUGGACGCCCGGGCGACUACGUGUACAUUUUCCGUUCCUUCCGAAUGGAAGAGUGUGCGCCAGGGGGCUGCCUGAUGGAGCUAUGCAUCCAGCUCAGCAUCAUCAUGCUGGGGAAACAGCUGAUCCAGAACAACCUGUUCGAGAUCGGCAUCCCGAAGAUGAAGAAGCUCAUCCGCUACCUGAAGCUGAAGCAGCAGAGCCCCCCUGACCACGAGGAGUGUGUGAAGAGGAAACAGCGGUACGAGGUGGAUUACAACCUGGAGCCCUUCGCGGGCCUCACCCCAGAGUACAUGGAAAUGAUCAUCCAGUUUGGCUUCGUCACCCUGUUUGUCGCCUCCUUCCCCCUGGCCCCACUGUUUGCGCUGCUGAACAACAUCAUCGAGAUCCGCCUGGACGCCAAAAAGUUUGUCACUGAGCUCCGAAGGCCGGUAGCUGUCAGAGCCAAAGACAUCGGAAUCUGGUACAAUAUCCUCAGAGGCAUUGGGAAGCUUGCUGUCAUCAUCAAUGCCUUCGUGAUCUCCUUCACGUCUGACUUCAUCCCGCGCCUGGUGUACCUCUACAUGUACAGUAAGAACGGGACCAUGCACGGCUUCGUCAACCACACCCUCUCCUCCUUCAACGUCAGUGACUUCCAGAACGGCACGGCCCCCAAUGACCCCCUGGACCUGGGCUACGAGGUGCAGAUCUGCAGGUAUAAAGACUACCGAGAGCCGCCGUGGUCGGAAAACAAGUACGACAUCUCCAAGGACUUCUGGGCCGUCCUGGCAGCCCGGCUGGCGUUUGUCAUCGUCUUCCAGAACCUGGUCAUGUUCAUGAGCGACUUUGUGGACUGGGUCAUCCCGGACAUCCCCAAGGACAUCAGCCAGCAGAUCCACAAGGAGAAGGUGCUCAUGGUGGAGCUGUUCAUGCGGGAGGAGCAAGACAAGCAGCAGCUGCUGGAAACCUGGAUGGAGAAGGAGCGGCAGAAGGACGAGCCGCCGUGCAACCACCACAACACCAAAGCCUGCCCAGACAGCCUCGGCAGCCCAGCCCCCAGCCAUGCCUACCACGGGGGCGUCCUGUAGCUAUGCCAGCGGGGCUGGGCAGGCCAGCCGGGCAUCCUGACCGAUGGGCACCCUCUCCCAGGGCAGGCGGCUUCCCGCUCCCACCAGGGCCCGGUGGGUCCUGGGUUUUCUGCAAACAUGGAGGACCACUUUCUGAUAGGACAUUUUCCUUUCUUCUUUCUGUUUUCUUUCCCUUGUUUUUGCACAAAGCCAUUAUGCAGGGAAUAUUUUUUAAUCUGUAGUAUUCAAGAUGAAUCAAAAUGAUGGCUGGUAAUACGGCAAUAAGGUAGCAAAGGCAGGUGCUUUGCAGAAAGAAUGCUUGGAAACUUGAGUCUCCCUAGAGGUGAAAAGUGAGCAGAGGCCCGUAGAAACCCUCCUCUGAAUCCUCCUAAUUCCUUAAGAUAGAUGCAAAAUGGUAAGCCGAGGCAUCGCGCAAAAGCUGGUGCGAUGCUUCAGGGAAAAUGGAAAACCCACGCAAGAAUAAUGAUUGAUUCCGGUUCCAAAAGGUGUCACCUACCUGUUUCAGAAAAGUUAGACUUUCCAUCGCCUUUUCCUUCCAUCAGUUGAGUGGCUGAGAGAGAAGUGCCUCAUCCCUGAGCCACACAGGGGGCGUGGGAGCAUCCCAGUUAUCCCUGGAAAGCUAGAAGGGGACAGAGGUGUCCCUGAUUAAGCAGGAAACAGCACCCUUGGCGUCCCCAGCAGGCUCCCCACUGUCAGCCACACACCUGCCCCCAUCACACCAAGCCGACCUCAGAGUUGUUCAUCUUCCUUAUGGGACAAAACCGGUUGACCAGAAAAUGGGCAGAGAGAGAUGACCUCGGAAGCAUUUCCACAGAUGGUGUCAGGGUUUCAAGAAGUCUUAGGGCUUCCAGGGGUCCCCUGGAAGCUUUAGAAUAUUUAUGGGUUUUUUUUCAAAUAUCAAUUAUAUGGUAGAUUGAGGAUUUUUUUUCUGUAGCUCAAAGGUGGAGGGAGUUUAUUAGUUAACCAAAUAUCGUUGAGAGGAAUUUAAAAUACUGUUACUACCAAAGAUUUUUAUUAAUAAAGGCUUAUAUUUUGGUAACACUUCUCUAUAUUUUUACUCACAGGAAUGUCACUGUUGGACAAUUAUUUUAAAAGUGUAUAAAACCAAGUCUCAUAAAUGAUAUGAGUGAUCUAAAUUUGCAGCAAUGAUACUAAACAACUCUCUGAAAUUUCUCAAGCACCAAGAGAAACAUCAUUUUAGCAAAGGCCAGGAGGAAAAAUAGAAAUAAAUUUGUCUUGAAGAUCUCAUUGAUGUGAUGUUACAUUCCCUUUAAUCUGCCAACUGUGGUCAAAGUUCAUAGGUGUCGUACAUUUCCAUUAUUUGCUAAAAUCAUGCAAUCUGAUGCUUCUCUUUUCUCUUGUACAGUAAGUAGUUUGAAGUGGGUUUUGUAUAUAAAUACUGUAUUAAAAAUUAGGCAAUUACCAAAAAUCCUUUUAUGGAAACCAUUUUUUUAAAAAGUGAAUGUACACAAAUCCACAGAGGACUGUGGCUGGACAUUCAUCUAAAUAAAUUUGAAUAUACGACA